GAUUUAGUAAAGACACAGGCGAAUCAAGAGGAGGCGAGGCCGGUAUUGUCCGUCUGAAUAGGCGCUGAUAGCGCCGAUGCGCCGGGGGUUGUGCCGGCGCAGCGCUGAGAAUCCCGACGCGGGGCCGGUACCCGGCGCGCCGAGGGGCUGGAGGGUGCUUUUUCCUCCCCUUGAGCGCCUCUCUUUUCUCUUUUUGGUCCCGUUUCGCCCCGAUCUCGCUCUCUUUUUGCUCCGGGUUUCCCUCCGACUGGCCCUCGAAAGGCGCCUGAAUCCGUGUCAAUAUAGCUGCUUCAAUUUCGCCGCGCGUGUCAGGCGGGCGGGCGGGCGGGUGCUCACCGCGCUCGGGGUUUUCUUUUCUUCAACCACCCUCCGCCCCUCACCCAUCUCUUUUUUAUUUUCUUUCUUUCUCUCUUUUCUCCUUUUUGCAUUUUGUGCCGAGAGGAGAAGGGAGCGAGGAAGGGGAGUGGGGUGGGGGGGCGGGUGGAGAGAGAAAAAAUUCGAUUUUUAAUUACUACCAUUAAAAAAUCAAAUUUGCAAUUCUUUGGGCGGCCUGAUGGAUCUCACUGAUUGACAGUUGGAAUUGACACUCUGGCUACCUCUUAUCUUGGGCAUUCACGACAAUUUCUAAUUGCAGGUGAUGGCCCAGCCAGGGUCCGGCUGCAAAGCGACCACCCGCUGUCUUGAAGGGACCGCGCCGCCCGCCAUGGCUCAGUCUGACGCCGAGGCCCUGGCAGGAGCUCUGGACAAGGACGAGGGUCAGGCCUCCCCAUGUACGCCCAGCACGCCAUCUGUCUGCUCACCGCCCUCUGCCGCCUCCUCCGUGCCGUCUGCAGGCAAGAACAUCUGCUCCAGCUGCGGCCUCGAGAUCCUGGACCGAUAUCUGCUCAAGGUCAACAACCUCAUCUGGCACGUGCGGUGCCUCGAGUGCUCCGUGUGUCGCACGUCGCUGAGGCAGCAGAACAGCUGCUACAUCAAGAACAAGGAGAUCUUCUGCAAGAUGGACUACUUCAGCCGAUUCGGGACCAAGUGUGCCCGGUGCGGCCGACAGAUCUACGCCAGCGACUGGGUGCGGAGAGCUCGCGGCAACGCCUACCACCUGGCCUGCUUCGCCUGCUUCUCGUGCAAGCGCCAGCUGUCCACUGGUGAGGAGUUCGGCCUGGUCGAGGAGAAGGUGCUCUGCCGCAUCCACUACGACACCAUGAUUGAGAACCUCAAGAGGGCCGCCGAGAACGGGAACGGCCUCACGUUGGAGGGGGCAGUGCCCUCGGAACAGGACAGUCAACCCAAGCCGGCCAAGCGCGCGCGGACGUCCUUCACCGCGGAACAGCUGCAGGUUAUGCAGGCGCAGUUCGCGCAGGACAACAACCCCGACGCUCAGACGCUGCAGAAGCUGGCGGACAUGACGGGCCUCAGCCGGAGAGUCAUCCAGGUGUGGUUUCAAAACUGCCGGGCGCGUCAUAAAAAGCACACGCCGCAACACCCAGUGCCGCCCUCGGGGGCGCCCCCGUCCCGCCUUCCCUCCGCCCUGUCCGACGACAUCCACUACACCCCGUUCAGCAGCCCCGAGCGGGCGCGCAUGGUCACCCUGCACGGCUACAUUGAGAAGGCAAGCGAUUCAGCAGCCAUUCAAAAAAUGCCUUCAAAGCACCCACAAUGUGCCAGUGCCCGGAGACUGGGGAGAGAACAGGCUGGACAAGGUACCUACUCUGUGGAGCCUGCGUUCUGGUGGGCAUGGAAAAAUAGGCAGAUGAGUGUGUCGUUUUAAGUGGGAUGAUUCCUGUAGGAAAGGUGCUGGGUAGGAGUGACUGGAGAUGCUGCGGGGUGGAAGGGAAGGGGCUGGGCUGCCUUUCAGCAAGCAGAGACUGAAAGGAUGGAUAGGAUUUAGUGAGGUACCUGGAGUGGGGGAACGGAAUGCACGCAGGCCCUGGCCCAGAAAGCAUCGUGGCAUGGGUGUGUUCUGGGGAGCAGAAGGCCAGUGUGAUGGGAGUGUCCAGGGCUGUGAGGCCUUAGGCAAGUCACCUAACCUCCUUGAGCCCUGGUUUCCUCAUCUGUAACCUGGGAUGUCAAUAAUGCCAGCCUCACAGGGUUGUGAGACACCAUUCAUGCAUUCAGUAGCUAUAUCUUGAGUGCCUUCUGUGUUCUUUGCACUGGGAUACGACAGUGAACACAGUAGACCAAAGCUUCUGUGCUCCUGGGGUUUGCACUCCAGCAUGGGAGAUGGUGGAGAUGAUAAAGUAACAGGGAGGGAGCAGGCAUGUCCGUGGCAGGGAGUACUGUGGCGGAGAUGCAGGGGCAAGCGGGUCAUGGUGAAGUGACUUGUGAGCGGGAACCUGGAGGAGUGAGGGAGGAGCCCCGGGGAUUUCUGGAGGAUGAGUGUUCAGUGAAUCUGCUGCUGAGCAGGUGCCUAUCACAGAUUGUCUUUCCCUUUGAAGUUGUUCCCAUCAAUUGUUUCCUCUAAGCUGGGCAUGACCAAAAAAAUGUAAAUGACUGCGAUGCACACAGACACAAUUCCUCCCUUCUCUGGCUCCAUGUAAGAGGGAAAAAGAAGGGAAAUCAGACAGAGAACUGCUGCUUACUGACCAUAUGCCAUAUAUUCUACUGACUGUGUCUCUAAACAUCAGAGGCCACCAUCUCCUUGAAUAGAUGAGGAAACCAAGGGCCCACUGUAAGUUAGUGGGAGCCGGUAUGCCUUAAUGAUCGAGUGUGGGCUUUGGUUUCAGAUUGCCAGGCUUCACAUCCCAGCCCUGCCAUUUACUAGCUGUGUGACAGUGGGUGAGUUUCUUAGCUUUCUUGCAUACUCAUUCCCUCAUCUGUAAAAAUGAGGACAACAGUAUCUCAAAGCAGUGUUCUGAGCAUCAAACGAGGUAACUGAAAAUCCUCAACAUUCAGCAAGUGCCGCAUAAGUAUUGGCUGCUCUUGUGAUGGUGGGAGUGGUUUUGGUUGGCAGAACUAGGAGUGCAGAGCCCUGUCUUCGCACCAGGCUGCCAGUUGGAAACCAUGUCUCUUUAUAUAGUUCCAUUUCUGAACUAUCUGCUCAAUAGGAGCGACAUUUUCCCCCUUUCUUUUCUAAACAAUAACUAUAUUCAGGCUGCACAGAGCCUGUUAAAGGUGCCAAGGAUCAGGGGCGCUAUAAGUACCAGGGGUCUGAGCUACCUGCUAAUACUUGGUGUAGAGUCAAUAAGAAAUCUAGAUGAUCCCUUUGGACUUGGGGCCAUGACCUCCAGAGUCCCUGCCAGGACUCUGUCCAUACACUCUGUUGACCAAACUUAGAUCUGUCUUUGCUGCUUAGAGAAGAGGCUGAGGUGCCCUCUCCUCUUACCCUUGUGGUGGAACUCAGCUUGGGGAAGAAGAGGUUGGGGGUGUGUGCACCUGCACCUCCUGCUGCAUGACUGACUGAGAGUCACCACAGCAGUUUGCUCUAUGGUAAACUACAGUCAUGGAGUUGUGAAUUUUCUGAAGCCUUAAGCUGGGAAGCUAAUGAAAGUGUUAGAACCAGACCCCAGAAAAAUGAGUUUUUCUGUAGAGUUUGCUCUGCGGUUAACUAAAGUCACAGAAUACUGAGUUUCCUGGAGGCUUCGAGCUUGGAAUCUGAUAAAAGCUUUGGAACCAGACCCCAGAAAAAUGCAGAUGUACAUACAUUUUCCAAGUAAUCUGAAGUUGUAUAUGGACUCCUUGAACACCCCAGGUGAAGAACUCCCAAUUUAAUAUAACUCCUUUAUUCUACAAAUGGGAGAACUGUGGCUCAGAAGGGCACAGUGAAUUGUCCCGGUUUAUAUAUCAGUUGUAAGUGUCUCUACAAUGCCCUUUCCCUGUGACCAAAGAGAAUGAAGCCUAAAGAAGAGACCAGCAAUGGACUUCUCCGCUGUAGUGAUAAACAGGCUGAAGCAUGAGAAAUUUGGAUCCGACCCAAAGGUGGACUUUCCCCAACAGUUUUAGAUGUUGGAAUAUGGUAUAGAAAUUCAUUCAGCACAUACUUAAGAGUACCUACUAAAUGCCAUGCCUCACUCUAGGUGCUGGAAAUCCACAAAGAUCUAGAAUCUAGAAAACAUACAAAAAAUUCCUGCCCUCGUGGAGCUUUGCAUUCUAGUUGGCAAAGACAGAUAAUAUCAAAUAAAUAAUAAAAAUAUGCAGUAAGUCAGG